GGAAGGGCUCUGUCCAUUACUUGCUGACAAGAACAAGACCUCAAACAUACACGGCACUCAAGAAAUAUCUGUUGAUGGAAAAGAAAUGGAUAAAUGACUCUCAAAGCUACUGAAAUACAUAUCUGAAAUAUAAGGACCAUGUCUCCUAAAGGUUCCUCUGCUUUUCCUUAUAGUAUUUUUCUUUCUUUCUUUCUUUUUUUUUUUUUUUUUUUUUUUUGCUGAAGUUUGACAGUACCCUCAGAUAUUUAGGAACCAUUAUAAUAGUGGGGUGGGACAGGGAACAGGUGAUUUCUUGUAGUUCUUUAAGUCUAUAAAAGUGAGUGGAAUCUAACUAAAUAUUGAUUAUAGAUUUCAAUAAAGUGGCUUAAAUAUUCAACACAUUCAUUUCAUUAAAUAAACUGUAAUCGUCUACAGCAAAUUAUUCUAAAACCAUCAACACUUUUUUUUUUUUUUACUUCAUCUUAGGGUUAAGGGAAUUUCUUGUGAUGACAAUAUUUUAUACAGUUCACUUUCAAAAUACAGCUUGAUUCCACCAUGAUUUUCUGUGUCAGUUUUAAAUUUUUGUCACUUUGUUUUUUUAAGAUAAGGUUUGUAACCUUAAGAUAUUCUCCUCCUGUUGUAAUUUCUUGAUUAUCUCUUUGUUAAUGUUAUUUAUGCUGCUCCUCUUUUAAUAUUUUAUCUUUCUAUUUACUUUUGCAAUUGCAAAGUAGUCCCAGAUAUUAUUCUUCAGUCACUCUCUACAUCCUUCUUUUGAUAUCAAAAGGCACAACUAGUGAUUCAAGAUGAGUGUAGAGCAGAAAGAAAUCUGGAAGACCUAAUUUACAGUUUUAUUUUCACCUUACAACUAUUUCCCUUUCAUCACUAGCAGCAUAGAUUUUGUCUAAAAACAACAUAGUGUUCAAACUCGUAGCUUCUAGUAGGUGCCACAUAGACAAUUAUAAAUACUCAUUAAUGAUUAUUAUUAUGCUUAUAUAAUGAUCACUUUAGAACACAUUCUAGUUCCAUACUCUUAAUUGUAUUGCAAGACAAAUAAAGCUCCUCUUUUUUUUUUUUUUUUUAAGUCUCUAAUAGUGAAAAUUUUGGCUUGGGCAAAAUACAUUUUUCUGUUUUAAUAUGAAAAUUACAAGUGUAUGUGUACAUACACAUGCAUAUAUUUUAUAUAUACACACACACACAUAUAUGUCAUAGUCCUACCCUAUGUGGACACCAAUAUUGUCCAAAUAAUAGAAAAUGGGAAGCAUACUUAGCUUUCUUGUAUCUUCCUUUAAACUUUGAUUUCUUUCCUCAAAUACAGACCAUUGGUCUGAAAUCCCUUCAUGACUUUUCUUUUUUUUGAGACGGAUUUUCGCUCUUGUCGCCAAGGUUGGAGUGCAGUGGUGCGAUCUCGGCUCACUGCAACCUCCGCCUACCUGGUUCAAGUGAUGCUCCUGCCUCAGUCUCCCAAAUAGCUGGGAGCAUAGACUCUCGCACCAUACCCGGCUAAGUUUUGUAUUUUUAGUAGACACGGGGUUUCACCAUGUUGUUCAGGCUGGUCCCGAACUCCUGACCUCAGGUGAUCCACCCGCCUCGGCCUCUCAAAGUGCUGGGAUUGCAGGCAUGAGCCACUGCGCCCGGCCAACCCACCACGCCCAGCCCCUCUCUUGAUUUUGACCAGAGGGUGCCUUUUAUUUAUCUUCUAAGAUAAACACUGGAGAAAGGGAGGAGAAUGAACACCGUUCAACUGCCUGCCCUGUGCCAGGUGCUGUCUGAGGCAAGGUGCAUGAGCUAUCUUUCAGCAAAUGAAUUCACCUCAGCUCCAUUGCCGUUUGUAGAGCUGCAUCCUGGCCCUCGGAUAUGAAGAGUCCAGAAAUAAAAAACACAGUAGGAGAAUGAUUUCAGCAAUUUCAAAAGAAAAACCAGCUUAUAUCCAGCUGCCAGCUAGAUAAAGUACCACUACAAUUAGAAAUAUUUUCCUAGCAACUUCAAACAUUGAAAAUAAUUAAAAUGUAAUAAUACUUAAUGUUUAAAACAGGGAACUCCCAACUGAUUAGAUGGUGAAAAUCUCACUCUUGUACAAAACAGACCAACCUAUAUUCAUUUUAUAUAUAUAAACUUUUAUUACUUUAAUUUUGAGAAAUUCCAAGAGUCCUAAAGAUAUGACAAUACCUGUAAAACCACUUAAAUAGCUGUUACUAAUAUUUUGUCAUUUUUCAUCCUAUUUUUAUUAAUAAAAGAAAACAUUACUAAUGAUAUUCAAGUUUCUAUACAACGUACCCCCCAUACCAUCUGCCCCCAGAAGUAAUCACUGAAUUUUGUAUCAUUCCAAUCCACAUUUAUAUUAUUAUAUGCACAUAUAUGAAAUCAUACUUUGCACAAACUUUUAAGAUUUCAGGCAGGGGAAUGAACUGCUCUCUGCCUUUCAUGCUUUAAACCCAGUCUUGUUCCCAUAACCUUGUGCAAACCCAGUUACAAUCCAGUUAUUUCAAAUUCUCUAAGCUGAAGUCCUUCGCCUUUUAAGUAGAGUUUUUGCUUGCAGGGAGCGUAUUUGCUCUCAAUGCAGGGACAGGCUGAAUGGAGUCCAAAGCGCUAGGGUUUCACAUUUGUAAGUGAUAAGAGGGGGAGGUGGUGACUUUCAGAGAUCAUGUUUCAAGUCCAGCCCUGGUUUUUAUGUGUGUGGGAAUGGACGCAAAGGAAAACACAGCUGAGCUGCAUUGUAACUCUUCCUGUAGAACCUGUUCAUGUCCAGGUUAUUCCAAUGGAAACAGCUGGAGAACUUAUAUUUCCGUGAGAAAAAAUUUGCUGUUGAAGUUCAUGAUCCACGAAGGAUUUCAGUUUCAAGAAGAACCUUUGGGCAAAGUGGCUUGUUUGUGCAAACAUGGUAUGCUAACUCUUCUCUCAUCAAGUCCAUUUGGGUAAUGGCAAUUAGUCAGCAUCAGUUUUACUUGGACCGGAAGCAAAGCAAAGCAAAAAUUCCUUCAGCCAGGAGUUUAGAUGAGAUUGCAAUGGAUUUGACAGAGACAGGAACACAAAGGGCCUCCAAGCUGGUGACACUGGAGACGAAAAGUCAGUUCAUCAUGGCAAGUAAUGGCAGUUUAAUCUCCUCAGGUUCUCAAGACUCAGAAGUUAGUGAAGAGCAAAAGAGAGAAAAAAUCCUUGAACUAAAGAAGAAGGAGAAACUAUUACAAGAAAAACUUCUGAAAAAAGUUGAGGAGCUUAAGAAGAUCUGUCUGCGGGAGGCUGAGCUCACAGGCAAAAUGCCAAAGGAGUAUCCCCUGAACAUAGGCGAGAAGCCUCCUCAGGUCAGAAGACGUGUGGGUACUGCGUUCAAAUUAGAUGACAACUUGCUGCCGAGUGAAGAAGAUCCUGCUUUGCAAGAACUGGAGAGUAAUUUUCUAAUACAACAAAAGCUGGUGGAAGCUGCAAAGAAACUUGCCAAUGAGCCAGACCUUUGUAAAACUGUGAAGAAAAAGCGAAAGCAAGAUUACACAGAUGCGAUGAAAAAGCUUCAGGAGAUUGAAAAUGCAAUAAACGAAUACCGAAUUAGGUGUGGAAAGAAACCCAGCCAGAAAGCAACAGUGUUACCAGAAGACAUAAUCCCCUCAGAGAGUAGCUCUUUGUCUGACACCACCACCUAUGAUGAUCCCAGUGAUGCCUUCACUUUUCCUGGGCAGCGAUCAAGUUCAGUACCUCAUUCUCCAAGAAUUCUUCCCCCCAAGUCUCUUGGUAUUGAGCGAAUCCAUUUCAGAAAGUCGUCCAUCAAUGAACAGUUUGUGGAUACCAGGCAGUCCAGAGAAAUGCUGUCCACACACAGCAGCCCUUACAAAACUCUGGAGAGGCGGCCCCAGGGAGGACGAAGCAUGCCCACCACGCCAGUUCUUACCCGAAACGCCUACAGCAGCAGCCACUUGGAACCCGAAUCUUCAUCUCAGCACUGCCGCCAGCGGAGUGGAAGCCUGGAGUCCCAGUCCCACCUGCUCUCCGAGAUGGACAGCGAUAAGCCAUUUUUCUCCCUCUCCAAAUCCCAAAGAAGCAGCAGCACAGAAAUCCUCGAUGACGGGUCUUCUUAUACAAGCCAAUCAAGCACAGAGUAUUACUGUGUGACACCAGUUACCGGCCCCUAUUACACCACCCAGACCCUGGACACUCGCACCAGGGGUCGGAGGAGGUCAAAGAAACAGAAUGUUUCUACUUCAAAUUCAGGAAGCAUGCCCAACCUAGCACAAAAGGAUAGUUUGAGGAAUGGUGUUUACUCAAAGAGUCAGGAGCCACCGUCUUCCAGUUACUACAUUGCCGGGUACACACCCUAUGCAGAGUGUGACUUUUAUUACAGUGGUGGUUAUGUCUAUGAGAAUGACACCGAGGGACAGUAUAGUGUCAACCCUUCCUACCGGUCCUCAGCCCACUAUGGAUAUGAGCGCCAGAGGGACUACAGCAGAUCCUUUCACGAAGAUGAGGUCGACCGGGUACCCCAUAACCCAUAUGCAACUCUCCGGCUGCCAAGGAAGGCUGCUGCAAAAUCGGAGCACAUCACCAAAAACAUCCACAAGGCCUUAGUUGCCGAGCACUUGCGUGGCUGGUACCAGCGGGCCUCUGGGCAGAAGGAUCAGGGACACAGCCCGCAGACCAGCUUUGACUCAGACAGGGGAUCACAGAGAUGCCUGGGGUUUGCGGGGCUGCAAGUACCUUGUUCUCCAAGCAGUCGUGCAUCCUCGUACUCUUCAGUGUCUUCUACAAAUGCUUCUGGGAACUGGAGGACCCAGUUAACCAUAGGGCUGUCGGAUUACGAGACUCCAGCACAUUCUUCUUACACCAGCUGCUAUGGCAAUGUCUAUAAUCCUUUACCCUCUCCAAGCAGGCAAAACCAAGGGCUUCUAUCCCCAAGAAUGGUUGUGUCUCCAGAAGUGAGAUCAGUUGUAAAUUCUCUUUUGCUAAGUGUAGCCAGCUGUAACAAUACACAGAAAUCAGUCAACUGGAUGGUACAGAUGGAAACCAGCUGGAAGACAACCUGGAGAGUAGUGAGCAGAGACUCUUUUGGCAUGAAGAUUCAAAGCCUGGAACAUUAGUCUGAACUGCAGUUGGACCUCCUGACCAAGCACUGCGUUCUCACACUAGUGUGCCUUGCAAAUUGUAUUUGUCUUCCGAGAGGAUGUUCGUUUUAGAAACCUAAAGACAUCAAAGGUUGAAGAGAAGACUUAGUUGCCCUGGAAGUGAAUCAGUGAAUCACACACCAAGCCCCACAAAGCCCCUAAAGGAGGAUUUGGCCUUUCAAACUCUAGGCACUAACGUAACUGUAGGGUCUGCCCACAUGUUGAAGUAUUGCCAAGAGAGGACUCAGUGUGAAGCCUUCAUCAAUAGCAAGCACUUUUUAAGGGAGUAAAAGUUGUUAAAGGCAAACCUCAAAAACAUGAAAGGGCAUUCAGGAUGUCCCAUGGCAAUAAGAACAGGGGAAAUCUCAGAGCACAAUUCAGCAGGAUGAGAGAAGGGGAACCAGAAGCUCCGGAGUCAUUGCUCACUUCAGAGUUUGAAUUCGUGAGCUGACAAAGAGUAACAUGCUCUUUCUACACAGACAUGGACAAUUUAGACAGUAUUGGAAAAUUACUUGAAGCUGGAUUUUCAUGAAGUUCUGAAUGAGUGUAAAUGUUUUUUAGGAUACUAUAAAGAGUGAUGUUUUUCAUAAGCACCAUAAAAUGGGUUCUGGAAAAACUGAUUACCUUAGCAUCCUGUAAUAUAACUUAUGGUAGCAGAUUGGGGAAAAUGAAGCAGCCCACUGAAUAAUUGACAAAGUCUGCUUGGAGAACAUUCUAAGGUACAAUAUCAUGGAGCUCCUUUUUCCUUUCUCCACUAAUUGCGUGAUGAGCUAUUGUUCUGGCUGUUAAUUCUCCAACUCGGCUGUCAUUUGAAGUGGCAGACUUAAUAUGGAAAGUUUUUAUAAUUAUGAGUUUGAAAAAGCAUUUUAAGAUGAUACAGAAAGUAUCCAAAACAACAGAAAAAAAAAGCCACGUCAUUUUAGAUGAAUUGCGUGCCUUAAAAUGGUGAACGUUAGAAAAUUAAACAAGUCUGGAUUCCACAAGUAGUUCCAAGUCACCAAGUGACAAAAACAAGGUUAACAUUAAAAAAGAAAAACAACAACAACGACAAAAAGCUCCAAGCUGCAGUGGAUUUAAUUAUGAGGCUAAAACUACCUCAUACUUUCCUUGGAAGAACUAAUUAGCUAUGGUUUAUUGUAGGGUUUUGUUUGUUUGUUUUUUAAAGCAAAUGAUUUCCAUAUUCCAGAUUGAUCUUUUUUGUCAUCUUUGCUUCAAAAUUACAUAAAAGGUGCUCCUUUCCCCCUUCUUUUAUACAAGUUUCUUGUUCAUAUUGUGAAUAGAAAAGUUUCUGAACAACUUUUUUGGAACAUUUUCUAUCUAUAUUCCAAAGCAUGUAAUAUAUACAUAAAAACGAUUUGUUAAACUGGUCCUUAGUCAUUUGUAUAAUUAGAAAUGAAGUUUGGGAAAAAAUUUUGGAAAAAAGACAAGCAAAAAAAAAUAACUUAUUCCUUUUUUGCAUAUUUGUAUAGCCUUCUAGAAUCAGAAAUAACCUUUUUGCAUAUUCUUUUAUUGUUCUGACUUUUCAAGACCUAUUAUUUUUUUACAUAGGUCAAUAAACAAAAGGUGUGCUACUGAAAAUGUUUACGUUUUCUUCCAUUUAUGUCAGGGGUUCAUGUGAAGCAGGUCGCAGUGCUCUACUUCAAGUAAUCAUAUUGGGCAAGGCUUCGGAUUUUUAUUUAUAGUAUUACCGUAUUUUAUUAAUUCCGGGAUGUACAUUUUUAAAUAUUUACAUUAAAAACAUGGUUCAUCUUUUUAUUGAUGGCAUAUUCUACUUGAAUUGGCAGUUUUUUCUUAAUAGUACAUUAAAAAUAAUGCUGUGUCUUACAAUAAAGUUGCCUUAGAAUUGAUGAAAUGCGGUAGUUUGUCUCACUGAGGAUGACUGGUGAGAACUUUUAGGUUUUUUAAUCUUGGGAAUGUUGUUUAUUUGUAGCAAGUAAUUUAUACUAAUUUCACAGACUGGCAAACAGGUCUUCUAAAUUCAAGAAAUUAGUUCUCUGACAUCCUUUAAUCCUACAUAAUGUGGAGAAGGGAGUGGAAAUGAAAUAUAUUUCCAUACAUGUAUCUUGCAUAAAAUAACAUUUUUCUGUUCCUGAAAUAGUAUGGUUACACUUGCAAGCAUGCCUUGAAAGGGCAAAUAUAACUUGGCUCCCACAGAGGAAAAGAAGGUAUAGAAAUGGAAGCUCAGGGCCAGGCAUAGCGGCUCACACCUGUAAUCCCAGCACUUUGGGAGGCCGAAGUGGGAGGAUUGCUUGAGCUCAGGAGUUCAAGACCAGCCUGGACAACAUGGUGAAACCCCAUCUCUAUGAAAAUACAAAAAUUAGCCAGUCAUGGUGAUGUGUGCCUGUAAUCUCAGCUACUUGGGAGGCUGAGUUGGGAGGAUAUCUUGAGCCCAGGAGGCGGAGGUUGCAGUGAGCCAGGAUCGUGCCACUGCAUUCCAGCCUAGGCAAUAACAGACCUUGUCUCAAGAAAAAAAAAAAAAAAAAAAAAAGAAAGAAAUGGAAGUUCAGCAAUCCUACUGCACGGUUUUCUUCGUCUCUUUUGAAAAACAUUUCUCAACCGCAUUGGUAUUAAACCAAUUAAACUACGUUAUUUAUUAAAAGCCAAAAGUGACAAAAGUACAUUAUUCAACAUGUACGUUUCCUCUUUUUUAUUACAAAAUACCAUGGUUAAAUGCAAAACCAAAAUAGUACAUAACAAAAACAUAAUCGUGCCCAUUAGCCGAACACUCUCAGAUAUAAUAGUUAAUUUAUUGUAUAUUUGUUUGGAUUUUUUUCUAUGCAUAUAGUAAUUUUUUUAAAGUCCAGCAUAUUACAAGUACAGUUUUACAACAUUUUUUUUUGUUUGUUUUGUUUUCUGCCUAAUAUAUCUUGGGCCUCUGUAUCAAGACAUACUGAUCUACCUCAUAAAGAUAUAUGUUUAACAAGGUGGAUUUUUAAAAUUGCCUCACCCUACUAGAUGUUUAUCUAUUUUUCUAUAUUUGACAAAAAUUUUCAAAAUUCUUCCUUGUACUCACAAAAGCUUAAAUAUUACAAGAAAUAAAGAUUCCGGAAUUGUUUUAAA